AGACAGAAUCUGAACCUCUGUGUCUCUCAGUCUUUCUCUCUUUCUCAUUCUCUUUCAAUAUGGAACUUGAAAAGCGUGAAAAAAGAAGCUUAUUAAACAAGAAUUUAGAGGAGAAACUGACGGUCUCUGCUGGUGGUUCUGAAGCCAAACCUCUGAUCUUCACAUUUGUCCCCACUGUCAGAAGACUACCAACCCAUACUCAGUUGGCUGACACCUCUAAAUUCCUUGUUAAAAUUCCAGAAGAAUCAAGUGAUAAGAGUCCAGAAACUGUAAAUAGGUCUAAAUCCAAUGACUACUUGACCUUGAAUGCUGGGAGCCAACAAGAGAGAGACCAAGCGAAAUUGACUUGUCCUUCAGAGGUCAGUGGAACGAUUUUACAAGAAAGGGAAUUCGAAGCAAACAAACUUCAAGGGAUGCAGCAAAGUGACCUCUUCAAAGCUGAAUAUGUCCUUAUUGUGGACUCCGAAGGGGAAGAUGAGGCUGCAAGCAGAAAAGUUGAACAAGGCCCCCCAGGGGGGAUUGGCACCGCAGCUGUCCGGCCCAAGUCUCUAGCUAUCUCGUCCAGUCUGGUCUCUGAUGUAGUGCGUCCCAAAACACAGGGGACUGAUCUCAAGACCUCAUCACAUCCUGAAAUGCUUCAUGGGAUGGCCCCUCAGCAAAAGCAUGGGCAGUUAACUUCUUCUCCCACUACCUCUGAGCAGCUUGCCUGUAAACCACCUGCUUUCUCCUUUGUUUCUCCAACUAAUCCGAACACACCACCCGACCCAGUUAACCUCGAGGGAGCCUCUGUCCUAGAGGAGUUCCACACUAGGAGGCUGGAUGUCGGUGGGGCCGUGGUGGAAGAAUCAGCUACGUAUUUUCAAACUACCGCUCACUCUACACCCUUUUCUGCAUCGAAGGGCACCUCCUCGACGUUACUGUUUCCCCAUUCCACUCAACUAUCAGGUUCUAAUUUACCCAGUUCAACUGCAGCAGAUCCAAAGCCUGGACUGACCUCUGAAGUUCUCAAGAAGACAACUUUAACCUCGCAUGUCCUUAGUCACGGAGAAAGUCCGAGAACCUCUUCUUCUCCACCGUCCUCCAGUGCUUCUCUGAAGUCGAAUUCGGCCUCGUACAUACCAGUCCGCAUUGUCACGCAUUCACUCUCUCCGAGCCCCAAACCAUUUACCUCCUCUUUCCACGGCUCUUCUUCCACCAUCUGCAGCCAAAUGUCAUCUAGUGGAAAUCUUUCAAAGUCAGGGGUAAAAUCCCCGGUGCCUUCCCGGCUUGCCCUUCUCACUGCCAUUCUCAAGUCAAACCCUUCCCACCAAAGACCCUUUUCCCCUGCAUCCUGUCCCACCUUCUCUCUCAACUCCCCGGCCUCUUCCACGCUCACACUUGACCAAAAAGAAAAGCAGACCCCACCCACGCCUAAAAAAUCUCUCUCAAGUUGUUCCCUGAGAGCCGGGUCACCAGAUCAAGGGGAACUCCAGGUUUCUGAAUUGACCCAGCAAUCUUUUCACCUGCCUGUUUUCACCAAGUCUACUCCGCUUUCUCAGGCGCCCUCCCUCUCUCCUACAAAACAGGCUAGUAGCAGCCUUGCUUCCAUGAAUGUAGAGAGAACACCAUCACCUACUUUGAAGAGCAAUACCAUGCUCUCCCUGCUACAAACCAGUACAUCCAGUUCUGUGGGUCUUCCUCCUGUUCCACCAAGCUCUUCUCUUUCCUCUUUGAAGAGUAAACAGGAUGGUGACCUCAGGGGUCCAGAAAACCCCAGAAACAUUCACACGUACCCUUCUACAUUAGCCUCCUCUGCAUUAUCUUCUCUAUCUCCUCCUAUUAAUCAAAGAGCUACGUUCUCUUCUUCAGAGAAAUGUUUCCAUCCUUCCCCAGCUCUUUCAAGCCUGAUAAACAGAUCUAAAAGAGCAUCAUCCCAACUAUCUGGCCAGGAGCUGAAUCCUUCAGCUCUUCCUUCACUCCCUGUCUCCAGUGCUGACUUUGCCUCUCUUCCCAACUUGAGGUCCUCCUCUCUCCCUCAUGCCAAUCUGCCCACCCUGGUGCCCCAGCUCAGUCCCUCAGCUCUGCACCCACAUUGCGGCAGUGGUACCUUGCCUUCAAGACUUGGGAAAUCUGAAAGCACCACCCCCAACCACAGGUCACCUGUUUCAACCCCAUCACUUCCCAUAUCUCUAACAAGGACAGAGGAGCUGAUUUCACCUUGUGCAUUGUCCAUGUCAACAGGCCCAGAAAAUAAGAAAUCAAAGCAAUACAAGACCAAGUCAAGCUACAAGGCUUUUGCAGCAAUCCCUACAAACACAUUGCUUUUGGAACAGAAGGCACUAGAUGAACCAGCCAAGACUGAAAGUGUCUCCAAGGACAACACAUUAGAACCACCAGUGGAGCUCUAUUUUCCUGCACAGCUCAGGCAGCAAACUGAAGAGCUCUGUGCUACCAUUGAUAAGGUCUUACAGGAUUCCUUGUCUAUGCAUUCUUCUGAUUCUCCUUCAAGGUCCCCAAAGACAUUGUUGGGUUCUGACACAGUCAAAACUCCUACAACUCUUCCAAGAGCAGCUGGUCGAGAAACCAAAUAUGCAAAUCUCUCCUCACCAUCUUCUACAGUAUCUGAGAGUCAGCUGACUAAGCCUGGAGUAAUUCGCCCAGUACCUGUAAAAUCCAGAAUAUUACUGAAAAAAGAGGAGGAAGUCUAUGAACCCAACCCUUUCAGUAAAUACUUGGAAGAUAACAGCGACCUCUUUUCUGAACAGGCUGCACAUUCUGUGGACUCCUACUGCAACGGAAGUGACACGUCUGGUCCUUGGCUCCUCUGAUCAUUGAGGAACCCUAUCCUUGUGGCUAGUUACUGUAGCCUUUGACUUUCCUACUUCCUGAAAAAGAGAAAAAGACGAUGAUAGAAUUCAAUGGCAAGAACAUGGGCUCUUGUGAUUUUUGAAAAAAUCAGUCCUUACUGAACUUCAAUUUUAUCCUACAAAAAUGGGGCUACUAAUCACCAUUUCUAAUGGAACCCAUACUAAUAAGUAUUUGUGAUUUUUUUAAAAGUAUAAUUUCUUUAAAUUUUUUCCAAGUGCUUUCAUCUUUAUUGCAGUAUAAUUGACAAAAAUUAUACCUAUUUAAGGUGUAAAAUGUGAUGAUUUGAUGUAUGUGUACAUUGUAUAAUGAUUACCACAGUUAAAUUAAUCAAUGUAACUAUUAAUGUACUAGUUACUCUGUGUGUGUAUAUGGGAGAAGAGAUGAGGACACAUAAAAUCUAUUCUCAGCAAAUUUCAAGUAAAAAGUAAAAUAUUAUUAACUGUAGUCACCAUGCUAUACAUUAGCUCUCCAGAACUUAUUCCUUUGAUAACUGAAUGUUUCUACCCUUUAAACACCAUUUUUCCUUUUCACUUAAAUCCCUUAUUAAGACAAUAAUAGAUUCAAAACAACAAAACAUCCAUUUCAACCAAAAGUCCAUUCCAACCCCUGGCAACCAUCAUUCUACUCUUUGCUUCUGUAAUUCUGACUAUUUUAGAUUCCACUAAAGUGAGAUCACGCAAUAUUUGUCCUUUUGUGACUGGCUCAUUUCACUUGGCAUAAUAUAUUUGGAAUUCAUUCAUGUUAUUGGAAAUGGCAGGAUUUCUUUCUUUUUUAAGGCUGAAUAAUAUUUCAUUGUUUAACACGUUUUAUUUAUUCAUUUAUCCAUCAACAGACACUUCGGUUGUUGCCAUAUCUAAUUGUUAAGAAUGAUACUGCAAUGGUUGAAUGAAAUACUCACUAUCAAAGGGCUCUAAAGACUUAAAUGUUUCUUGUUAUCAUUUCCUUUAGAAUCACUUCAAUUUUGGAAGAAAGAGGUUGAUUUCCUGCUAAAGGGUCAACUGAAUAUAUUGUCUUCUUUCUCUCUUCCAUUAUGAGCAAUUGUAGAAGCCUAUUUUCUAUGUUACUUUUGACUUCUUCAAUUUUAACUGCUCCUCCAUCCUAAACACCUCCACAUGGGAAAUAAAAGACCAGAAUCCAACUAUAUGUAUAGAAAAACAUAAAACUCAGCAUUGUAGUCCUCUGCUGCUCACUGUGAUUGAUUAUGGAGUGUUUUUCUUUCUUUUCCCUUGAGUGUACCUCCAUCAGAUACUUCCAUGCUGAUCCAUGCCAUCUGUUCUGUGAAACUUGCUGUCAGACAACCAUACACUUUAAGCACUAAGUUAUCCAAAUUCUAUCUUAAAAAUUAUGUUGUGAUUAUUAAAAAUCUUUUUUUAUAUAGAGGAUUUCAAAUAGCUAAGCAUAUGCUAAAUUUUUCAUACUUCACAAGUUCAAAUUUUCUUGGUUCAAAUCAGGAUUCAAAAUAUAUGUGUUGCUUUAAAUAUGUCUGUUUGAAAAAAUGCAUAUGGAUUCUCCAAAAUUUGGGUUUCUAAGCAAGAAGAUAUGCCAUAUAAUCGAAACCAAUUUAUAUUGGCUUUAUCUUAGUGAAAUGUAGAUAAUCACAAUCUCUUAUUUCAUAGUAACAUGAGGUUUUUGUGAUGCUGUCUGUAAAGUGUUGGUGUCUUUAGAUAAAGGGGUCGCUCUUUAAGAAAAUAUUACUACUGUUCAUGAUUUUAUUAGCAAGGUGUUGAUUUAAAUUAAAACUGUAGCAAAAAUGCUAUGGCUCUGAUUUUAAACUGCUGUAAGUUCUAGACAGCAAAGGAAAGCUGAAAAUAAAUGCUGCAUUUAAAAAUAAAUGUUGCUUUACCAAAGAGGUGGGAAGAUGGAAGACAGGAUGGAGUGAAAGGCUCCAGUAAUUUUACCUAUGGUACUCUGAGUUCACAAAGGUGUCUUGUACUCAGACAGAAAACCGCAGCGUGAAGAGGGGACAGCAUGAGUGAAGAGGAAGUGAAUUUUCACCCUUCACUUCCAAACCACAGGAAAGGAAGUGACUUUAAAAUGCCAGGAUGGAACAAAAGCAUUUCAGAUGUGCAGGCUUUAAUAAGAAGAGCUCAAAAUGCCGUAAAAUGCCCUUUGAUGUUGCAAUGGAAACAGUUUUUGAAGUUAAACAGUAUGAUUUGAUGGUUGAGUAGAAAGUAGGCUUUUUCUAGAGCACCAAAUGCAUCAGAUAUGGCUAUAACACUAAUUUUCUGAUGUGUCUGUCAGUUAAGCAGAGCUAAAUUAAUAUAUUCACUGCAUAUUUGUCUGCUAAUUUUUCUUUAAUGAACAAAGAUAUUACUUGCUUCAUAAGUUCCUGUCUUCUUGAAGUUUUGUAGAAUGAUAGUAUCAUCUCAAAAAUAAUUAAUUCUUUUCAAAAAUCAAGCUCCUCAGUAAAGCCUUUUUUUGAAACAUUAGUUCUAUGUAUACUGAAAUUGAAAGAGGACAAUUCUCAAGUGACUAAAAAGCGGUUUAAAGCAUUUUAUCAGAAAUAACUAUGUUACCUAUCUCAUUGAUAGAAACAUGUCCAAGACUGUUUUAUGAUCCCUGUACAUCCCUCAAAAACUAAAACAUUAAAAGAUUCAUAUAUUGCAUGCUAAAGCAGGAUAGAGUGAUGUUCAUUUUCAAGAAUCAUUUAGAAUAGUGAUCUCUAAAGUAUUAGGUACCAACCUCAAGAUAAUUCGCUGGGGUGGAAGUAGGGCACAAGUUAGACGUGAUAGAGAUGCCAUUAGUGUGUUUUGAAGCAAAUCUCAAACAGGGGUCACAAACUAUGGUCUGUGGGCCAAACCUGGCUCACCAGUGUUUUUAUAAAUAAAGUAUUAUUGGAACAUG